GACCUUAAAUAUAUCGAGGUGGCUAAUUGAUGUAUAAUAAUUUACAAAAUUAUUCUUCUAUGCUACAGAGCUACAAUUCAAUUUACAGUAGUAAAUAUGAGGGCCUUCUUAAGGAACCAGAAAUAUGAGGAUAUGCACAAUAUUAUUCACAUUUUACAGAUCAGAAAAUUGAGGCACAGAUUAAGUAACUUCCCAAGGCUACCAGGCAUUCUAGCUCCAGAAACUGUGCUCUUACCAUUCUGCUACAAGGUAUUUCGAAAAAAAGAAAAAGUAAAAAGAAGUCAAAAGGCAACAGAGUUCAUUGAUUAUUCCAUAGAACAGUCACACCAUGCAAUUCUCACACCCUUGCAGACACACUUGACCAUGAAAGGUUCCUCAAUGAAAUGUUCCUCAUUAUCUUCAGAAGCCAUAUUAUUCACAUUGACUUUGCAGUUAACUCAGACCCUAGGUCUGGAAUGCUGUCUUCUCUACUUAUCCAAAACUAUACAUCCACAGAUCAUAUAAACUCUCAGCCCUGCUGCAAAGCCUUUCCAGAAAAAUAAAAAUGGUUGAAAAGGCAAUUCUGCUACCAAUGACUGUUUAAGCCCAGCCAAGUAACUGAACCAUUCCAACUUCAAUUUACUUAUGAAAAGAAUUUGAUGAUGUAGGAGGUUAUUUCAAUUCUAAAAUACAAACCCAUGUUGAUCUUUCUCAAUCUUGAACUCAUAGAUUAUUAUCUAUUAUCUCAAUUUAGUUUGUUAUUUAUCCUAGUGGGCCAUUAAAAACUACCACAUGUGUUUCUGUCUCUCCAUUAGUCAAUAACUAAACUAACGAGCAAUUAGUAAGCCAUGUGCCAGAUGCUCCGCUAGGCACCAGAGGGAUAAAAACAAUACUUAUAGUAUACCACUAAUUUUCGCUUAGUAACUAGUGAAAUGUUCAAGUCAUGCCUGAGUCAAGAGUUGAGGAGACAUUACAAUGUGUAAUGGAAACCAAGGAAAGUGAAACUUUGGAUAAGUGGGGACUAGUGUAUUUAUAUAUUUAAUUGAUUUCUGACUCUAUCAUUGGCCUCCAAACACAGAUUGUGUUUUUCUUUGGUUUUGUUUUCUUCACUAUGGGAUCUUCUGUGCCCAGCACAGUGCCUGACACAUAGAAAACAAUCAAAUAUUUGCUGAAUAAAUGAUUAAAAAAUCAGAGAACUUUCCCAUUCUGUUUGGAUCUAUAGAACAUCCAGAGUAAGUGAUGAGGGCCUCUGCAUUUAUAUGCGCUUAAAUUAAGAUUAUGUGAGAAAAGUUUAAAGACACUUAGUAGAGUGAUUUUGAAAUAUAGUAAACACUUGGAAAUGGUGGUGCUUUAAAAAGAUAUUAAUAGAUAAUAUGAAAAUCUCCAUCUCAAAAAUAAUGCAUAAACUAUUUAAAGGAAAAUCACAUCUCCAGGCUUUCAAUGUUUGUUCAUUACUUUUUCAUAUAUUUUUACCAUCUGCUGAAGGCAGUCAUAUCAAAGGGUAAAGAAAGAUGGGAGGAAAACUCAGUAAGAAUUAUAUUAGUCUGUUUGCAAAGUAGAAAAAGAUUCUCAUCACUCAACCUUAUGAGCAGGAAGAGGGAAGGCUGUUUGAGAACCAUUUACUUAGCAGAACCACAUAUUUUAGACACUUCCCUGCAUUAACUGCACAAACAAUAUGUUUGCAAACUUGUUAGAUCAACCUCCAACAACGACACAUUCAGGAGUUAAAUAUUUUUCAUCAAACAUUGGAUUUUUCCUUAACGCUAGAGAUUGCUACAAAUCUUCUGAAGGGUCUCAAUGGCUUCAGGCUAAGAAGAGAUUUCUCCCUGUUAUAAGCAGCAAGACAAAUUAGCCAUUUCACUCUCAAACUUCACUAAUGAUCACAUUCUUUCCAAAAGGAACUCUAGAAGACCAAAUGCCCCGAGUUAAGAACAUCAAAACUAACCAUCUGAAGAAACUUCCCAAGUGUAAGACUCUGCCAUUAAAACAUUACCGAGAGGGGACUCAAACAGUCUUUCUUCCUUUGUCGUGUUUCUUGCUCCCAGACCAAGGCACUGACGACAGUACUGAUACAUAAUUUAAAAGCACACUCCCUUCCACUUUGUAAUACCAGAACUCUAAUUGGACACCCUGAAGCUUAGGACUACCAGCCAUACAAAUAGUAAACUCUGUCCACGAUUCACUCAUCUGUGUAUUUUCUAUAGAUGUUUACUAGGCGUUUGUUAUAUAAAAAUACCCCGGCCAGGCACGGUGGCUCACGCCUGUAAUCCCAGCACUUUGGGAGGUGGGUGGAUCACCUGAGGUCGGGAGUUCGAGACCAGCCUGACCAGCAUGGUGGAACCCCCAUCUCUACUAAAAACACAAAAAAUUAGCCGGGCGUGGUGGCACAUGCCUGUAAUCCCAGCUACUCAGGAGGCUGAGGCGGAGAAUUGCUUGAACCCGGAAGGUGGAGGUUGCGGUGAGCUGAGAUUGCACUAUUGCACUCCAGCCUGGGCAACAGGAGUAAAACUCCCCCCCACCCAAAAAA